ACCAGCCUGGACAGCCAAAGGGGUCUGUGUGUGGCCGGGGAGGAUGGCGGGGGAGUGAGCCCCAUGGAACAGCCAGGAACUGAUAAAAGAUGAGGGGACAAAGACAGUGUGUGUCUGGGAAGCUGGGCUGAGAGGAGGAGGUGCCGCCGCCUGGGGGUACUCCGAUGCUUCCGGGGAUUCCGAGCCAGCUGGAGGACCGCACGUGGCGAACGGCGGGCGCGGCGCGUAGUCAGGGAACCAGGGUGCCUGACUGGGUGUCUCGUGGAGCCAUCCCGCGGGGGUGUGGGGGGGCCACGGUGCCGGAAGGCGCGCGGCCCAGAGGCCGUCUCCGCCGAACGCCCGCUCCUCGCCUUCCUAACCGCAGCACUUUCGCGAGCCUCCCUACGAGGGGCGGGGCGAAACAGCAGCCAGCCCCGUGUCCGGCAGUAUGUUCAGCUGGGUCAGCAAGGAUGCCCGCCGCAAGAAGGAGCCGGAGCUCUUCCAGACGGUGGCUGAGGGGCUGCGGCAGCUGUACGCGCAGAAGCUGCUACCCCUGGAGGAGCACUACCGCUUCCACGAGUUCCACUCGCCCGCGCUGGAGGACGCUGACUUCGACAACAAGCCUAUGGUGCUCCUCGUGGGGCAGUACAGCACGGGCAAGACCACCUUCAUCCGACACCUGAUCGAGCAGGACUUCCCGGGGAUGCGCAUCGGGCCCGAGCCCACCACCGACUCCUUCAUCGCCGUCAUGCACGGCCCCACUGAGGGCGUGGUGCCGGGCAACGCGCUCGUGGUGGACCCGCGGCGCCCCUUCCGCAAGCUCAACGCGUUUGGCAACGCUUUCCUCAACAGGUUCAUGUGUGCCCAGCUGCCCAACCCCGUCCUGGACAGCAUCAGCAUCAUCGACACCCCCGGGAUCCUGUCUGGAGAGAAGCAGCGGAUCAGCAGAGGCUAUGACUUUGCAGCCGUCCUGGAGUGGUUCGCGGAGCGUGUGGACCGCAUCAUCCUGCUCUUCGACGCCCACAAGCUGGACAUCUCCGAUGAGUUCUCGGAAGUGAUCAAGGCUCUGAAGAACCAUGAGGACAAGAUCCGCGUGGUGCUGAACAAGGCAGACCAGAUCGAGACGCAGCAGCUGAUGCGGGUGUACGGGGCCCUCAUGUGGUCCCUGGGCAAGAUCAUCAACACCCCCGAGGUGGUCAGGGUCUACAUCGGCUCCUUCUGGUCCCACCCGCUCCUCAUCCCCGACAACCGCAAGCUCUUUGAGGCCGAGGAGCAGGACCUCUUCAAGGACAUCCAGUCACUGCCCCGAAACGCCGCCCUCAGGAAGCUCAAUGACCUGAUCAAGCGGGCACGGCUGGCCAAGGUUCACGCCUACAUCAUCAGCUCCCUCAAGAAAGAGAUGCCCAAUGUCUUUGGUAAAGAGAGCAAAAAGAAAGAGCUGGUGAACAACCUCGGAGAGAUCUACCAGAAGAUUGAGCGCGAGCACCAGAUCUCCCCUGGGGACUUCCCGAGCCUCCGCAAGAUGCAGGAACUCCUGCAGACCCAGGACUUCAGCAAGUUCCAGGCGCUGAAGCCCAAGCUGCUGGACACGGUGGAUGACAUGCUGGCCAACGACAUCGCGCGGCUGAUGGUGAUGGUGCGGCAGGAGGAGUCCCUGAUGCCUUCCCAGGUGGUCAAGGGCGGCGCCUUUGACGGCACCAUGAACGGGCCGUUCGGGCACGGCUACGGCGAGGGGGCCGGCGAGGGCAUCGACGACGUGGAGUGGGUGGUGGGCAAGGACAAGCCCACCUACGACGAGAUCUUCUACACGCUGUCCCCUGUCAACGGCAAGAUCACGGGCGCCAACGCCAAGAAGGAGAUGGUGAAGUCCAAGCUCCCCAACACCGUGCUAGGGAAGAUCUGGAAGCUGGCCGACGUGGACAAGGACGGGCUGCUGGACGACGAGGAGUUCGCGCUGGCCAACCACCUCAUCAAGGUCAAGCUGGAGGGCCACGAGCUGCCCGCCGACCUGCCCCCGCACCUGGUGCCGCCCUCCAAGCGCAGACAUGAGUGAUGGCGCCCGGCCCCGCACCUGCCAUUUGCACGCCCGGCCGGGAGGCAGAGACGGGGGGAGGGGAAGCCUCACCAUUUCUCAAGGUCCAUAAAGACUGAGCGGAUGUUUCCUCGCCUCUCGAAAAGGAAAACCACCAUCUUUCUUUUAAGGCUGUUCCUGGGCCUGGCGGGGGAGGCAGGGGUGAGAGGAUGGAAUUGUGUGCACAAGAACUGUGGCUAUUUUAAUAUAUAACGUUAGAGGCUGCGUUCUUUGUCGCCGCCUCCCCUGUGUGCCAGCCCUGUGUGCACGGCCUCUGCCCCCCGGCCUUUGCUGUGGCUGGAGCUGGACAGUGCAGCGACUGCGACCGUGGGGGAGCCAGGUCGCCCUUUUGGCAGCUGCUAGGCUGAGGCUGCAUGGACAGGAACACCAGGCACCCUCCGUGUGCUUCUGAGCUGAGGUUGCUUCACGGGACCGUGGCUUCCUUCCUCACCUGGCUCUGCCUCCCCCGUGCUCUCGGGCGAAGUGGGUUCUUGUGCCUUCCCCUCCCGGGCCCAGGCUCCCCGUGCGCGGGCCCUGCCCUUUCCUCCCGCGCCCCACCGGCUCCGACGCGCAACCCCGCUCAGCAGUCACAGAAGCAGGGCCCAGCCACCUUGGUCUUUUUUUGGGAGUUCAGGGGAGUAGGAGAAUGUCUUCCAGAAAAAUACAUAAGCUAGUUUCUGUUCUGUAAAGUGAUAUCUUUCAUACUUGACCAAAGUUCCCAAUAACUUCCCAACCACUGUUCAAAAGCUGUGAUUUUUGUCUCCCCUUCCCACCCUCCAGCCAAGGAGCAGCCCUGCCCAGGGGGCAUUAGGUGUGGGUACCCGGGGAGCACCCCGUUCCUGGACCCCAGUGUUGCAUUUCCUGGCUGAGGAAGGGUGGUCAUCCCAGCUCCUGCCCUACCCUCUCACUUAACUGGAGCUUUGGGACGCACCCUCCACAGUGGGAGGUGGUGGUGGGUGGCGGUGGCGGGGCCUCACGACAGCUUGGUGCUGGUAAGAGGAAGCCCGUGGUUCUGGCUAGGCUCUCAUGUCCAGACAGCGGGGACCAGGGGAAAACCCAGCCCCUUCUGUAAUCCCCCUUCAUUUCCUACCUUCCUUCCUCCUCUGUUUAGCAAAGGAGGGCAGCUCACUUGGAUGUCCUUACAACGCCCCUGGCCCCCAGGUUGAGCAAUAAGAAACCAGAACCUUGCGGCCCAGUGGCCCGGGCCAGUUCAGGCCGCCUCCCCCUCCUCUGCCUGGGGCCAUUGAGCCCAGCCUCCAGGGCCCGGGCGCGUUUGCAGGCCAGUGGCCACUGUCCGGGCUGUGAUGGCACCAAGGCAGGUGGAGCACCAGGUACCACACAGCUGGGCUUCCCACCAGGCUUUCCCGCGGGGGUCUCAGGGAGCUUCUCCCCAGCGCUGCUCGGAGUCUGCAGGAACUGGCCUUGUUCUCCUUAGCCCGUCACUCCAUACAGUAUUAGGUGAGGAUGGAUGCGGGCGCUGUCCUUGCCGGGAAGUCACUGUUGAAGUUGCAGUGGCUUGUUCACACCUGUGGGAAGAGAAGUGAAGACUUUCUCCUUGCAUUAAAAAGUCUGAACUGUGCGAAAGCUUCGGGUGCUUCCUUGUCUUUUCCAGGGGCAGCAGUCCUGGGCCAUCCUCCCCUGGUGUCUGAGGGGGUGAUGCCAGCAGGGACAGAGUGGCAAGGCAGCCGGGGCAAGGUGACCAACCCUGCCCAGUCCUGCUCUGCUGGGCAGUAGCUGCCCCCUCCUACUAAGAGGGCCAGGCCUGUAGGGAAAAGGGUUUCUGGGGUGAUGCCCCCUUCCCUGAGCAAGGUGGGAGCUGAGCAGUUCACUUGGGGUGGGGAGGGGGGAAACAGUUGGGAGGAUGUUGAUAGCUGAGGCCUAGGCUGGCACCCCUCAGCCACAGACGGAUGAGUGGGCACCUGCAGGCCCUCGGCACUGGGUGGCAUCAAGUAAACAAGGGUUUCUGGGCUUUGGAGCCAGACUGGCUCCUUGCUAGCCCCAAGGACGGUUUAAGUACAGGGAAGCCGGGCCUCUGAAGACAAAGCAGAUAGCCUGUGACAAACAUGCAACUAAGGGUGGGGCCAGUCAGGCCCAGGUGAUGUCACAGAUGGGGGACUGUUUAUACCAGCAGAGGGAAGGGUGACUGAUUAGUGACCCUUCAUAAAAGGGUGCAGACUUGAGGUGCCAUGGGUAGAGGCUGCUCCAGCCCCUCUGGCAGAAGGCAGGACAGAAACAAGUUCCUGAGGGUUUCAGGGACCCAGUUGUGUGCUCCGAGCCUAGCUGGUGUGGUGGUGUCUGGUCCUAUGACCAGCACUUGAGGUGCCAGUGGAUGCUUCAGUUGCUGCAGGGCUGGCCGGCCCUCCCUGCGUCACUCAGCUGCCACCUGUGGGCAUUCACCCUGUGCCAGGUGGAGCUGCGCUGUCACGAUCUGAGGAAGUUCAUGUUCCCCCAUUUCACAGAGGGAGAGUCCGAGACUGAGGACUGCCGAAAUAACAAAGGUGGUAGAAGCAGAUGCAAACCAGGCCGUCCAACUCCAGCGUGCUUUCCAUCAGGUUACUAAUCCAAAGCACACACUAAGAGGAAAAAACGGUAGAUCCCCCCAACCCCACCCUUAGACUGCAGCUGUACUCAGGGCUGAGAGACCCACAUUAAAGGUUAAAUGCUGUCACUCCA